GAGCGCAUUUUGACUUCGAGGCACCGCCGACGUUACUGUGUCGCCAUGGGGCGCCGUCCAGCUCGCUGUUACCGGUAUUGUAAGAACAAGCCGUACCCAAAAUCUCGUUUCUGCCGAGGGGUUCCUGAUGCCAAGAUCCGCAUCUUUGACCUGGGUAGAAAGAAGGCAAAAGUGGAUGAGUUCCCACUCGGUGGCCACAUGGUGUCUGAUGAAUAUGAGCAGCUGUCUUCUGAAGCCCUGGAGGCCGCCCGUAUUUGUGCCAACAAAUACAUGGUGAAAAGUUGUGGCAGAGAUGGCUUUCACAUGCGAGUGCGGCUCCAUCCCUUCCAUGUCAUCCGCAUCAACAAGAUGUUGUCCUGUGCUGGGGCUGACAGGCUCCAGACAGGUAUGCGAGGUGCCUUUGGAAAACCCCAGGGUACUGUAGCCCGGGUCCACAUUGGUCAAGUCAUCAUGUCCAUCCGCACCAAGCUUCAGAACGAGGAGCAUGUGAUUGAAGCCUUGCGCAGGGCCAAGUUCAAGUUCCCUGGACGCCAGAAGAUUCAUAUCUCCAAGAAGUGGGGCUUCACGAAGUUUAAUGCUGACGAAUUUGAAGACAUGGUGGCCAAGAAGUGCCUCAUCCCUGAUGGUUGUGGAGUCAAGUACGUUCCCAGUCAUGGCCCCUUGGACAAGUGGCGGGUUCUGCACUCAUGAAGGUUUUGGCAGUACUGUCUCCUUGGGCCAUGCUGGUCUGACUUAUGCUUACUAAUAAAUUCUGUUUACUGGCAAAAAAUAA